GAGGUCUUAUUCUGUAGUCUAGACUGGAAUGCAGUGGUGCAAUCACAGCUCACUGCAGCCUUGACCUCGCUGGGCUCAGGUGAUCCUCCCAUCUCAGCCUUCUGAGUAGCUGGGACCACAGGUGUGUGCCACCCGCCCAGCUAAUUUUUAUGUAUUUUUUGUAGAGAUAGAGUUUUGCCAUGUUGCCUAGGCAGGUCUCCAACUCCAGGGUUCGAGCAAUCCACCCAUCUUGGCUUCCCAAAGUGCUAGGAUUACAGGCAUGAGCACCACACCCAGCCAUUUUUUUAAAUUUAAAUUUUAUUUAUUUAUUUAUGAAUUAAUUAAUUAAUGACAGGAUCUGACUCUGUUGCCCAGGCUGGAGUGCAGUGGCACAGUCAUGGCUCACUGAAGCCUCAAACUUCUGGGCUUAAGCGAUCCUCCCGCCCCAGCCUCCUGAGUAGCUGUAGCUGGGACUACAGGAAGACAGGACCACAUACAGCUAAUUUUUUAUUUUAUUUUAGGGAAAGGUGCUAUCUCUCUGUGUGUUGCCCAGGCUGGUCUUGAGCUUCUGGGCUCAAGGGAUGCUCCUGCCUCAGCCUCCCCAAAUACUGGAAGCAACUGUGCCUGGCUAAUUGCCUCUAAUCCUCAGAACAACCCUGUGAGAGAGGUUGUGCUAUUACUCUCAUUUUACAGGUGUGUAAACUGAGGCGUAGAAAGGCUGAGUGACCUCUCCCUGCCUCACUCUGGGUCCUCAGCCACUUCUUGCCUCUGCACGUGUUUUUUUUCUUUCCCUUAGGCAGGGAUAAAUAAAGGGCAUGUAUGUUGUCUUCUGGGGCCUGUAGUGAGAGUAGUGCAUUCUAUUAAUUAUGAUUGGUUUUGUUGUCAUGGCUCCUAAAAAUGAUGGGCUAGCAGGAACUACUGCAGUACCAAGGUUUCCCAUUUCCCCCAUGGGCCUGAUCCUAGGGUAGCAGCUUCCCAUUCCUCUGCAGUGGUGCCUGCAGCCACAGAUUUAAUUUAAAAAUUUCUAGUAGCCGCUGUGCAGUACAGUCUCAAACUCCUAGGUUCAAGUGACCUCCCUGCCUUAGCCUCCCAAGUAGCUGGUACUGCAGGUGCACACCACUGUGCCCAGCAAAAUUAAUUUUCGUAAUAGAGUUUAAUCCCUUACAUCCAAAAUAUUAUGAUUAUUUUUGGAGACAGGGUCUCACUCCUGUUGCCCAGACAGGAGUGCAGUGGUGCGAUCAUGGCUCACUGUAGCCUUGACUUCCUAGGCUCAGGUUAUUCUGUCAUCUUAGCCUCCGAAGUAGUUGGGACUACAGGCAUGUGCCACCAUGCUUGGUUGAUUUUUUUGUAUUUUUUGUAGAGACCAGGUUUUGCCAUGUUGCCCAGGGUGGUCUUGAACUCCUGGUCUCAAGCAAUCCACCCGCCUCAGCCUCCCAAAGUGUUGGAAUUACAGGCAUGAGCCACCGUGCCUGGCCCUUCCAAAAUAUUGUUUCAACAGGUAAUCAGUAUAAAAGUUAUUAAUGAAAUAUUUUACAUUCCUUCUUGAUAGCAAGUCUUCAAAAUCUGGUAUGUUAUAUUUAUAGCACAUCUCAAUUUGGACUAGCCACAUUUCAAUGCCCAGUAUCCUUGUAUAACUAGUGGUUACUGUACUGGACACAUCAGUUCUUUUUUUUUGAGAUGGAGUCUUGCUCUGUCACCCAAGCUGGAGUGCAGUGGCGCAAUCUUGGGUCACUGCAACCUCCAUCUCCUUGAUUCAAGUGAUUCUCCUGCCUUAGCCUCCUGAGUAGCUGGGACUACAGGCAUGCACCACCAUGCCCGGCUAAUUUUUUUUUUUUUGUAUUUUUCACCAUGUUGGCCAGGGUGGUCUUAAACUCCUGACCUCAAGUUAUCCUCUGGCAUUGGCUUCCCAAAGGGCUGGGAUUACAGGUAUGAGUCACUGUGCCCAGCCUGGACACCUCAGUUUUAGAAUAUACCCAUUUGAAACCUUUGAACUCAGUUUGGUGUACUGAUUUGAUCUACUGUCAUUGAGGGUGGUCCUGAGCUGAUUUUGCUUUGUAAUAUUAUUGCUAGUUAUUAGACAAGUUCUGGCUUCCUGCCUAGAUUUUUCUAUGCUAACUGGGCAGGUCCAAGAGUAAUUCUGAGGGUCUCAGACAAAGCCAAUAUCUACAUUUAUUAUGUUCACAAUUUUUUCUUUUGACUAGAAAACCGAAUUGACCUCAGAUUUUUUUUUUUUUUUUGGUCACAUCUGUUAAUUUGAGUUGCUGCCAAUAAAAAGAUAAUAUCCAGGCAAGUUCCAGCCUUGUUUAGUUAUAAGAAAUUUUGUUACAACAAGGCUGACUUAGGAAUUCAGUAAGCAUUCUAUUAUGAUAUUUCCUAGGGUUUGUGAAAUUUAGAUUACAUUUAAAAAAGGCAAACAUUAUGACGAUUUUGGUUCCAAGUAUUUCUGGAGUUUCUACUGUGUGCCAAAUAUUGUUCAUUCAAUGGAUUAAUAUUUAUUGAGCUUUUUUUUUUUUUUUCUGAGACGGAGUCUUGCUCUAUUGCCCAGGCUGGAGUGCAAUGGCGGAAUCUCGGCUCGCUGCAACCUCUGCCUCCUGAGUUCAAGUGAUUCUCCUGCCUCAGCCUCCUGAGUAGCUGGGACUACAGGUGCCAGCCACCAUGCCUGGCUAACAGAAUGCCCUUUUAAUGCAGACUUUAAAAGCGAUAAAAGGGUUGCCGCAUCUUUUACUUCUUAAGUCUUUCUCUCCUUAUGUGGUGGGAUGUCCUCAGGUUAUGGUUACUGAAAGAAAGUUAUCCUAGAAGGAAGUUUUUCAUCAGCUUUAUGUCCCUGGUAGAUUUGGGAAAGAAGCUUUUAGAAGCGGCACGAGCAGGUCAAGAUGAUGAAGUUCGUAUUUUGAUGGCAAAUGGAGCUCCCUUUACUACAGACUGGCUGGGAACUUCUCCACUUCAUCUAGCAGCACAGUAUGGUCAUUAUUCCACCACAGAGGUACUGCUGCGAGCUGGUGUGAGCAGAGAUGCCAGAACCAAAGUGGACCGAACACCAUUACAUAUGGCAGCUUCUGAGGGCCAUGCCAGCAUAGUAGAGGUUUUACUUAAGCAUGGUGCUGAUGUCAAUGCAAAGGACAUGUUAAAGAUGACAGCUCUCCAUUGGGCCACAGAACACAAUCAUCAAGAGGUGGUGGAACUUUUAAUCAAAUAUGGUGCUGAUGUACACACGCAAAGUAAAUUUUGUAAAACUGCAUUUGAUAUUUCAAUAGACAAUGGAAAUGAAGAUUUAGCAGAGAUAUUACAGAUUGCUAUGCAGAACCAAAUCAACACAAACCCAGAGAGUCCUGACACUGUGACAAUACAUGCUGCAACACCACAGUUUAUCAUUGGACCUGGAGGGGUGGUGAACCUAACAGGUCUGGUAUCUUCAGAAAAUUCAUCCAAGGCAACAGAUGAAACGGGUGUAUCUGCUGUUCAGUUUGGAAACUCUUCUACAUCAGUAUUAGCUACAUUAGCUGCCUUAGCUGAAGCAUCUGCUCCAUUGUCCAAUUCUUCAGAAACUCCAGUAGUGGCCACAGAAGAAGUAGUUACUGCAGAAUCUGUGGAUGGUGCCAUUCAGCAAGUAGUUAGUUCAGGGGGUCAGCAAGUCAUCACAAUAGUUACAGAUGGAAUUCAGCUUGGAAAUUUGCACUCUAUUCCAACCAGUGGAAUUGGUCAGCCCAUCAUUGUGACCAUGCCAGAUGGACAACAAGUAUUAACAGUACCAGCAACAGACAUUGCUGAAGAAACUGUUAUAAGUGAAGAACCACCAGCUAAGAGACAAUGUAUCGAAAUAAUUGAAAACCGGGUGGAAUCUGCAGAAAUAGAAGAGAGAGAAGCUCUUCAGAAACAGCUGGAUGAAGCAAAUCGAGAAGCACAAAAAUAUCGACAGCAGCUCCUAAAGAAAGAACAGGAAGCAGAGGCCUACAGACAGAAGUUGGAAGCUAUGACUCGUCUUCAGACUAAUAAAGAAGCUGUUUAAUUGAAAUGAACAUGUAGUUUGAUUUUACUUUUGGUCAAGAAAGAAUACAAUCUUGAACUGUACACAACAAAGGUACAGCCAUGGGAAUACAGAAUGAUAGAAGAGACUACAGAUGGAUAAUUGGACUUAAGCCAUGAGCUCUGAGUUCUUGUAACAUAAAACUUUACUUUAGAAGUUGUGAAAUGUAUUUAAAACUGAAUUCUGUAAAUAGUUUUUUUUUUUUUACAGUUCCAAAUGAGUUGAUAAAGAUUGUUGAAGAGAUCCAAAACCAGAAUAAGCCACUGUUUUUGUGAAUUCUUUUUGAUUUUAGUACAAACCUUAAUUUCUCAGAAACGGAACAGUUUUAAGGGUGAUCGUUGUUGGUUAGGCCAAAUGUUGUGUAAUAAUUAUGGUGGACUGAUGCUGGAAUUACUCCUGUAGGUAUAAACCUCUGUAUGAAGAGAAGAUUUCUCCCAGGAAAUCUUUGUACAGCUUUAAGUUGUGUCAGAUUCUCUGAAAACAUUUUUUAGAAAGCAAAAUUUUUAUAUUUGUUCAAUUUCAGCUAUACCCAAGUAGAUUUACAUGUAUAUGAAGCAAAUAUUUUUAAAAAUUUCUGUUUGUACAUAUUCUGCAUGUUUUAUAAUUUCAAAAUGCAUCACUUACAUAGGUAUUUCUCCCACAGAAAUGAUGAAAGUGACCAGAAAAAAACAAAAACAAAACCCCUUUACUCUGUAGGUCAUUGAAACGAAGUAAGCUGGCAGCUGGUUUUAUUGGAAUGACAGUGUUCUCGGAAGGAGCAGCCUACAAGAUAACUUGAAUUUGCCAAUUCUGCAAAAUCUGUGCUUUUUUGAAAAUUUAAGAGUGGGGACGUGAAACUGUAUUCUGUGCCUUCCAUCAUGAUUUCCACAUGAAAGCACUUUAAGGCACUGAUUUUAAGAUAAUGUUUUUGGAAAACCCAAUGCAUAUGGGUUUCUGAAAUAUUUUAUGGACUUAUUUCUCCCCAGGAAAUGAUUCUUACGGAAAAAAAUUGCUUUUGUAUGUAGAACAGGAACUUUUUGUAUUACAGUGAUGCAAUAGACAUGUCUAAUGUAACUUCUACUUUUCCUUUUGAAAGCUCAGUGUCUGUGCUAUGACUUGCUCUCAUCACAAUAUUGUUGAAUUCCACAAUGUAUGGACAUUAAACACUGGCAGACUGUUCACUUUUUCUUUUUUUUUUUUGGUAAAAUAUUACUUCAAACCCCUUUUUCUUGCUUUAUUUUUCAGUGUUUUAUUGCUUUAUGAACUGUUUAACCCUGAAAUCCCUCUAGGUUAUCUAUACUGUAUAAAAAAGCAAUUACCCUUAAAACUGUACUCUGGCCUACUUUUCUAUUUUGCAAUUAAAUAUCUUUUUCACAUAUGUUCAUUGUAGACUUAUGUUUUUAUCACAUCUUAUUAACACAUUAAAAAUGUUAUCCUACUGCAUAUUUGAGCCACCAUAUGAAAAUAUUUUAUACUCUCCACAACAUGACUUUAAAAUUCCUGAGGUAACUCUUGAGAAUUUGUUAACUCUUUCACUGGAAUUACCAGUAUAUUUGUUAAUGUAAUAAAGGGGUCUAUGGUCUGUCAGCCUGAUGGUUACUAUUGGAAGCACUUAAAAAAGAGUUUAGGGCAAAUUGAAGAACUCUGUAAGGAAGAGGAAAAAGAUCUUUUUCAAUUUUCCACUAAAUUUGACAUAUUUUAAGUGAUCCAAAAACUAGUUUUUAAAAAUGCCAGGCCAUAUUUUCAAUAGCAUGAAGUGACUUUUUCUGCAGUCCUGAAAAGUCAAUAGAGAAUGUUGUUUCUGGUUACUUCGGUACAUUAAUUUGUCAUGUUAGGCAGGGUGCUGGUACCACAGCCAGGUACCCUGACAUGUGGUGCUGGAGCAGAGAAGGGCCAGUGUCUUCACCCCAGAGGGCAAUCACUGUAGAGUUUUGCUUUCAGACCAGGCUGGCCCUGAAAAGACUCAAGACAGUGUUGGGAACAAGUUUGUGAAAGCUAACUUAAUGUCGUCUUUGACUUCCAGUCUCCUCUCCUGCUGGAGACUUUACCUGGUGCAAGAAAUAAUUUUGAUUCCUAAUAACAACAGCUGGCAUAGAUGGGAGAAAAUAAUUGGUGCUUAAAAGGAGUAAGUCUAUGAUAGCAUCAGGUACUCAGGUAUCUGUGGAGGAAGCUCACCUUUUUCAGAGUCAUUGUUACAUAACAUAAUUUCUCAAUCAUUUACAUCUGAUUUACUGUUCUGUAAAAUCACUACUUAGACAAGAAUUUGUAAUUAAAACUUAAAAUGGGUGUCUUCUUCCCUUCACUUAUUUCAUGCUGUUUUCAGGUGGGCUGUAAAAGCUUUGCAUUCUAGUCAUUCUCAAUAGUGCUCUGAACAGAGGAUUUAAAGAACUGACAAAAAUAAAAGUAUAUGAAAUAAAAGUUUUCAGAAAUCCACAUAAUUGUUUCCACUACAUAGUGAUGGAUUUGUAGUUAGCAGUCAUCUGGUUGCCACAUCACUGGUUAAUUGUUUCCACAUAUGUGUGAACAAACACCUGGAGCAACCUUUCUCAACCAGGGUUCUGCAAGACAAGCCAUUUAGUGUUAUGGUGUAAUGAAUUAUUUUCUUUCCUGUGCACCUAGAAUCGUUCUUGUUACGUACUAUCCAGACACUGAGUUCGUUAGGCAUCUUGACUGCCCAAUUACUUUAUUCAGAUUUAACACUUCCCUCUGUAUAGUCCCUGGACCUCUAGAAUUAUAAAUUCUAGACUGAAUCUGUGAUGCUUUCAGAAAGCCUCAUCUGAGAAGUAGUAUCUGCAGGGACUGUGCUUCUCAACUAAUUUUCAUUUAUUGUUAUUUAUUUUAUUUAUAUCUUAAUUACUUCACAAAAGGACUUGUGAUGUCAUUUGUUUUCGUUGGCUUUUAGGAAUUAUUUUCUUAACAUCAAUCUUUUGUGAUAUGAAUGGCAGAAGAGUUCUUUUACUCUGUCACUGGAUUGCUCUAUUUCUUUAUGGUGGUGGAGGGUUGGGAAGACAAUUAGAGAGAAAAGAGGAUAAAUGGGAAAUCUCAUGUAAUGAAAGCUACACAGAUGGUCCCCAAUUUAUGAUGCUUUGAUUUAUGAUUGUUUGACUUUACAAUGGGUUUAUCAGGGUAUUAAUUGCAUUUUACAUUUAUGAUAUUUUUGACUUAGGAUGGGUUUAUCAGGACAUAACCCCAUUGCAAGCCAGAGAGCAUCUGUACUUGUUUGUAAUAAAAAGAUCUGCUUACAAA